UGCCGCGGCAACCAGCACACCCCGGCACCUCCUCUGCGGCAGCUGCGCCUCGCAAGCGCAGUGCCGCAGCGCACGCCGGAGUGGCUGUAGCUGCCCGGCGCGGCGCCGCCCUGCGCGGGCUGUGGGCUGCGGGCUGCGCCCCCGCUGCUGGCCAGCUCUGCACGGCUGCGGGCUCUGCGGCGCCCGGUGCUCUGCAACGCUGCGGCGGGCGGCAUGGGAUAACGCGGCCAUGGUGCGCCGAGAUCGCCUCCGCAGGAUGAGGGAGUGGUGGGUCCAGGUGGGGCUGCUGGCCGUGCCCCUGCUUGCUGCGUACCUGCACAUCCCACCCCCUCAGCUCUCCCCUGCCCUUCACUCAUGGAAGUCUUCAGGCAAGUUUUUCACUUACAAGGGACUGCGUAUCUUCUACCAAGACUCUGUGGGUGUGGUUGGAAGUCCAGAGAUAGUUGUGCUUUUACACGGUUUUCCAACAUCCAGCUACGACUGGUACAAGAUUUGGGAAGGUCUGACCUUGAGGUUUCAUCGGGUGAUUGCCCUUGAUUUCUUAGGCUUUGGCUUCAGUGACAAACCGAGACCACAUCACUAUUCCAUAUUUGAGCAGGCCAGCAUCGUGGAAGCGCUUUUGCGGCAUCUGGGGCUCCAGAACCGCAGGAUCAACCUUCUUUCUCAUGACUAUGGAGAUAUUGUUGCUCAGGAGCUUCUCUACAGGUACAAGCAGAAUCGAUCUGGUCGGCUUACCAUAAAGAGUCUCUGUCUGUCAAAUGGAGGUAUCUUUCCUGAGACUCACCGUCCACUCCUUCUCCAAAAGCUACUCAAAGAUGGAGGUGUGCUGUCACCCAUCCUCACACGACUGAUGAACUUCUUUGUAUUCUCUCGAGGUCUCACCCCAGUCUUUGGGCCGUAUACUCGGCCCUCUGAGAGUGAGCUGUGGGACAUGUGGGCAGGGAUCCGCAACAAUGACGGGAACUUAGUCAUUGACAGUCUCUUACAGUACAUCAAUCAGAGGAAGAAGUUCAGAAGGCGCUGGGUGGGAGCUCUUGCCUCUGUAACUAUCCCCAUUCAUUUUAUCUAUGGGCCAUUGGAUCCUGUAAAUCCCUAUCCAGAGUUUUUGGAGCUGUACAGGAAAACGCUGCCGCGGUCCACAGUGUCGAUUCUGGAUGACCACAUUAGCCACUAUCCACAGCUAGAGGAUCCCAUGGGCUUCUUGAAUGCAUAUAUGGGCUUCAUCAACUCCUUCUGAGCUGGAAAGAGUAGCUUCCCUGUAUUACCUCCCCUACUCCCUUAUGUGUUGUGUAUUCCACUUAGGAAGAAAUGCCCAAAAGAGGUCCUGGCCAUCAAACAUAAUUCUCUCACAAAGUCCACUUUACUCAAAUUGGUGAACAGUGUAUAGGAAGAAGCCAGCAGGAGCUCUGACUAAGGUUGACAUAAUAGUCCACCUCCCAUUACUUUGAUAUCUGAUCAAAUGUAUAGACUUGGCUUUGUUUUUUGUGCUAUUAGGAAAUUCUGAUGAGCAUUACUAUUCACUGAUGCAGAAAGACGUUCUUUUGCAUAAAAGACUUUUUUUUAACACUUUGGACUUCUCUGAAAUAUUUAGAAGUGCUAAUUUCUGGCCCACCCCCAACAGGAAUUCUAUAGUAAGGAGGAGGAGAAGGGGGGCUCCUUCCCUCUCCUCGAAUGACGUUAUGGGCACAUGCCUUUUAAAAGUUCUUUAAGCAACACAGAGCUGAGUCCUCUUUGUCAUACCUUUGGAUUUAGUGUUUCAUCAGCUGUUUUUAGUUAUAAACAUUUUGUUAAAAUAGAUAUUGGUUUAAAUGAUACAGUAUUUUAGGUAUGAUUUAAGACUAUGAUUUACCUAUACAUUAUAUAUAUUUUAUAAAGAUACUAAACCAGCAUACCCUUACUCUGCCAGAGUAGUGAAGCUAAUUAAACACAUUUGGUUUCUGAAUAAAUUGAACUAAAUCCAAACUAUUUCCUAAAAUCACAGGACAUUAAGGACCAAUAGCAUCUGUGCCAGAGAUGUACUGUUAUUAGCUGGGAAGACCAAUUCUAACAGCAAAUAACAGUCUGAGACUCCUCAUACCUCAGUGGUUAGAAGCAUGUCUCUCUUGAGCUACAGUAGAGGGGAAGGGAUUGUUGUGUAGUCAAGUCACCAUGCUGAAUGUACACUGAUUCCUUUAUGAUGACUGCUUAACUCCCCACUGCCUGUCCCAGAGAGGCUUUCCAAUGUAGCUCAGUAAUUCCUGUUACUUUACAGACAGGAAAGUUCCAGAAACUUUAAGAACAAACUCUGAAAGACCUAUGAGCAAAUGGUGCUGAAUACUUUUUUUUUAAAGCCACAUUUCAUUGUCUUAGUCAAAGCAGGAUUAUUAAGUGAUUAUUUAAAAUUCGUUUUUUUAAAUUAGCAACUUCAAGUAUAACAACUUUGAAACUGGAAUAAGUGUUUAUUUUCUAUUAAUAAAAAUGAAUUGUGACAAAAGUGGACUCUGGCUUCCCCUCCCCCCUCCCCCCCACCCCUCUGGGAUAAAAAUUUUCCAGCAUUGCCAGGAGCUUUCAGGUACACAUUAAAGAAUAAAAUGAAGUUAAGCAGCUGGAGUAUAGGAUAGUAUUUGAUUUUCAAGAUCACCCAAAGCUGCACUAUCGUCCCAAAGC